AUUCAGGUACCAGGUAGCCCCAAGGAGGAGCUGCCGACCUGGCAGGUAAGUCAAUACCUGGGGCUUGCCUGGGCCAGGGAGCCCAGGACUGGGGUGAGGACUCAGGGGAGCAGGGAGACCACGUCCCAAGAUGCCUGUAAAACUGAAACCACCUGGCCAUUCUCCAGGUUGAGCCAGACCAAUUUGAUGGCAGAUUUAGCAAAUAAAAAUACAGGACACCCAGUUAAAUGUGAAUUUCAGAUGAACAGCAAAUACUUUUUUAGUAUUAAAAAAGUUCACAUUUAGGCUCACGCCUGUAAUCCCAGCACUUUGGGAGGCCGAGGCAGGCAGAUCACCUGAGGUCAGGAGUUCGAGACCAGCCUGGCCAACAUGGUGAAACCCCAUCUCCACUAAAAAUACCAAAAAUUAGCCAGGCGUGCUGGUGGGCACCUGUAGUUCCAGCUACUCAGGAGGCUAAGGCAGGAGAAUUGCUUGAACCUGGGAGGCAGAGGUUGCAGUGAGCUGAGAUCGCACCAUUGCACUCUAGCCUGGGCGACAAGAACAAAACUCCAUCUCAAAAAAAAAAAAAAAAAAAAAGUUCACAUUUAACUGGGCAUUCUGUAUUUAAUUGGUAAUCUGAGAUGGCAGGGAACAGCAUCAGCAUGGUGUGAGGGAUAGGCAUUUUUUCAUUGUGUACAGCUUGUAAAUCAGUAUUUUUAAAACUCAAAGUUAAUGGCUUGGGCAUAUUUAGAAAAGAGUUGCCGCACGGACUUGAACCCUGUAUUCCUAAAAUCUAGGAUCUUGUUCUGAUGGUCUGCACAACUGGCUGGGGGUGUCCAGCCACUGUCCCUCUUGCCUGGGCUCCCCAGGGCAGUUCUGUCAGCCUCUCCAUUUCCAUUCCUGUUCCAGCAAAACCCAACUGAUAGCACAGCAGCAUUUCAGCCUGUCUACCUCUGUGCCCACAUACCUGGAUGUCUACCAGCCAGAAAGGUGGCUUAGAUUUGGUUCCUGUGGGUGGAUUAUGGCCCCCAGAACUUCCCUGUGCUUGCUGGGGGUGUGGAGUGGAAAGAGCAGGAAAUGGGGGACCCUCCGAUACUCUAUGGGGGUCCUCCAAGUCUCUUUGUGCAAGUUAGGGUAAUAAUCAAUAUGGAGCUAAGAAAGAGAAGGGGAACUAUGCUUUAGAACAGGACACUGUGCCAGGAGCAUUGCAGAAAUUAUAUGGUUUUCACGACAGUUCUUUUUGGUAGGUACUGUUAUUAUCCUCAGUUUGCAGAUGAGGAAACUGAGACCCAGAAAGGUUAAAUAACUUGCUAGGGUCACACAAGUCAUAACUGACAAAGCCUGAUUCAAACCCAGGUCUCCCUAACCUUUAAGGUUUCUAUGACGCCAGCUCUCCUAGGGAGUUUGUCUUCAGAUGUCUUGGCUCUAGGUGUCAAAAAAAGACUUGGUGUCAGGCAGGCAUAGGUUCAAGUCCCAACUCUGUCACUUACCAACUGUGACUAGGUGAUUGAACUGACCAUGGAACCUGGUCACAUGCAGGAGCAGGAUGGUGAAGGGUUCUUGAAGGCACUUAGGCAGGACAUUUAGGCAGGAGAGAAAACCUGGAAACAGAAGAGCUGUCUCCAAAAAUACCCACUGGGGAAGCAGGUUGUCAUGUGGGCCAUGAAUGGGACCUGUUCUGGUAACCAAGCAUUGCUUAUGUGUCCAUUACAUUUCAUAACACUUCCAUCCUACUUUACAGGGAACAACCAAGACUGGGGUUAAAUCUCACAGCCUGCAAGUGGAAGAGAAGAACUUGAACCCAGGUCCAACUUUUGCGCCACAGCAGGCUGCCUCUUGGUCCUGACAGGAAGUCACAACUUGGGUCUGAGUACUGAUCCCUGGCUAUUUUUUGGCUGUGUUACCUUGGACAAGUCACUUAUUCCUCCUCCCGUUUCCUCCUAUGUAAAAUGGAAAUAAUAAUGUUGACCCUGGGUCUGAGAGAGUGGAUUUGAAAGUACUUAGUGCAUCACAAAGCACAGAACACACUUCCAGUCUCGUGAUUAUGUACUUAUGUAACUGGUCAUCACCCAUCUUGAGAAUGAAUGCAUUGGGGAAAGGGCCAUCCACUAGGCUGCGAAGUUUCUGAGGGACUCCUUCGGGCUGGAGAAGGAUGGCCACAGGAGGGAGGAGAGAUUGCCUUAUCCUGCAGUGAUCAUGUCAUUGAGAACAGAGCCAGAUUCUUUUUUUCCUGGCAGGGCCAACUUGUUUUAACAUCUAAGGACUGAGCUAUUUGUGUCUGUGCCCUUUGUCCAAGCAGUGUUUCCCAAAGUGUAGCCCAAGAACCAUCUCCCUCAGAGCCACCAGGAAGUGCUUUAAAUUGCAGGUUCCUAGGCCACAGCCUGCACCUGCAGAGUCAGAAUCAUGGAGGUUGGGACCCAGGCACCUGCGUUUCUAACAAAUGCCUCGGGUGAUUCUGAUGCAAUUGAAAGUUUGAGAUCCACAGUUCUGAGACAAUAACAGAAUGGUUUUUCUAACCCCUGCAGCCCUGACUUCCUAUCCUAGGGAAGGGGCCGGCUGGAGAGGCCAGGACAGAGAAAGCAGAUCCCUUCUUUUUCCAAGGACUCUGUGUCUUCCAUAGGCAACAUGUCAGAAGGGGUGGGCACGUUCCGCAUGGUACCUGAAGAGGAACAGGAGCUCCGUGCCCAACUGGAGCAGCUCACAACCAAGGACCAUGGACCUGUCUUUGGCCCGUGCAGCCAGCUGCCCCGCCACACCUUGCAGAAGGCCAAGGAUGAGCUGAACGAGAGAGAGGAGACCCGGGAGGAGGCAGUGCGAGAGCUGCAGGAGAUGGUGCAGGCGCAGGCGGCCUCGGGGGAGGAGCUGGCGGUGGCCGUGGCGGAGAGGGUGCAAGAGAAGGACAGCGGCUUCUUCCUGCGCUUCAUCCGCGCACGGAAGUUCAACGUGGGCCGUGCCUAUGAGCUGCUCAGAGGCUAUGUGAAUUUCCGGCUGCAGUACCCUGAGCUCUUUGACAGCCUGUCCCCAGAGGCUGUCCGCUGCACCAUUGAAGCUGGCUACCCUGGUGUCCUCUCUAGUCGGGACAAGUAUGGCCGAGUGGUCAUGCUCUUCAACAUUGAGAACUGGCAAAGUCAAGAAAUCACCUUUGAUGAGAUCUUGCAGGCAUAUUGCUUCAUCCUGGAGAAGCUGCUGGAGAAUGAGGAAACUCAAAUCAAUGGCUUCUGCAUCAUUGAGAACUUCAAGGGCUUUACCAUGCAGCAGGCUGCUAGUCUCCGGACUUCAGAUCUCAGGAAGAUGGUGGACAUGCUCCAGGAUUCCUUCCCAGCCCGGUUCAAAGCCAUCCACUUCAUCCACCAGCCAUGGUACUUCACCACGACCUACAAUGUGGUCAAGCCCUUCUUGAAGAGCAAGCUGCUUGAGAGGGUCUUUGUCCACGGGGAUGACCUUUCUGGUUUCUACCAGGAGAUCGAUGAGAACAUCCUGCCCUCUGACUUCGGGGGCACGCUGCCCAAGUAUGAUGGCAAGGCCGUUGCUGAGCAGCUCUUUGGCCCCCAGGCCCAAGCUGAGAACACAGCCUUCUGAAAACAUCUCCUGCCAGCUGAACUGUAGUUAGAAUCUCUGGGCCUCUCCUCAACUGUCCUGGACCCAAGGCUAGGAAAGGGCUGCUUGAGAUGACUGUGGUCCCCCCUUAGACUCCCUAAGCCCGAGUGAGCUCAGGUGUCACCCUGUUCUCAAGUUGGGGGAUGGGUAAUAAAGGAGGGGGAAUUCCCUUGAACAAGAAGAACUGGGGAUAGUUAUAUUUCCACCUGCCCUUGAAGCUUUAAGACAGUGAUUUUUGUGUAAGGUUGUAUUUCAAAGACUCGAAUUCAUUUUCUCAGUCAUUUCCUUUGUAACAGAGUUUUACGACUUAGAGUCUGUGAAAACAGGCAAGGAGCCCGGGUUAAAAUAUCCCCCUAUUCGCCCCCAAAAUGCAAUAAAAGAAGAUAAAAGAGAGAGGA